GUUGGUGUGGGGCCCUCCUGGGUCUGGUCCUGUUCGACCCCCUCUGAGGCCCACCUGGAGGAGCGGCAGUUGAGUUUCUAUGCUAAUUGUUCCAAUAAUAGGAGCCGCCUUUUACUGCGGAGUCUUUGUGUGCCAGGCGCUGUGCUUAGGCUAGUAUGAUGUAGUGGCCUAUGUUGAAGUGUGGUCAUCCAAUGGAACAGAAAAUUAUUCAAAGACAUUUACAACACAGCUUGUGGAUAUGGGGGCAAAGGUUUCAAAAACUUUUAACAAACAAGUAACUCACGUUAUCUUCAAAGAUGGCUACCAGAGCACUUGGGACAAAGCUCAGAAGAGAGGCGUAAAGCUCGUUUCGGUGCUCUGGGUGGAAAAAUGCAGGACAGCUGGAGCACACAUUGAUGAAUCAUUGUUCCCUGCAGCUAAUAUGAAUGAACACUUAUCAAGCCUAAUUAAAAAAAAACGUAAAUGUAUGCAGCCCAAAGAUUUUAAUUUUAAAACACCAGAAAAUGAUAAGAGAUUUCAGAAGAAAUUUGAGAAAAUGGCUAAAGAGCUACAAAGGCAAAAAACAAAUCUAGAUGAUGAUGUACCUAUUCUCUUAUUUGAAUCUAAUGGUUCAUUAAUAUAUACUCCCACAAUUGAAAUUAAUAGUAGGCACCACAGCGCAAUGGAGAAGAGAUUACAAGAGAUGAAGGAGAAAAGGGAAAAUCUUUCCCCCACCUCUUCCCAAAUGAUUCAGCAGUCUCAUGAUAAUCCAAGUAACUCUCUGUGUGAAGCACCUUUGAACAUUUCACGUGAUACUUUGUGUUCAGAUGAAUACUUUGCUGGUGGCUUACACUCAUCUUUUGAUGAUCUUUGUGGAAACUCAGGAUGUGGAAAUCAGGAAAGGAAGUUGGAAGGAUCCAUUAAUGACAUUAAAAGUGAUGUGUGUAUUUCUUCACUUGUAUUGAAAGCAAAUAAUAUUCAUUCAUCACCAUCUUUCACUCACCUCGAUAAAUCAAGUCCUCAGAAAUUUCUGAGUAAUCUUUCAAAGGAAGAAAUAAACUUGCAAAGAAAUAUUGCAGGUAAAGUAGUCACCCCUGACCAAAAGCAGGCUGCAGGUAUGUCUCAGGAGACGUUUGAAGAGAAGUAUCGUUUGUCUCCUACCUUAUCUUCAACAAAAGGCCACCUUUUGAUACAUUCAAGACCCAGGAGUUCCUCAGUAAAGAGAAAAAGAGUAUCACAUGGCUCCCAUUCACCUCCGAAGGAAAAAUGCAAGAGAAAGAGGAGCACCAGGAGAUCUAUCAUGCCGAGGCUGCAGCUGUGCAGGUCGGAAGACAGGCUGCAGCACGUGGCGGGACCUGCCCUGGAGGCUCUUAGCUGUGGGGAGUCUUCAUAUGAUGACUAUUUUUCACCUGAUAAUCUUAAGGAAAGGUAUUCAGAGAAUCUUCCUCCUGAAUCUCAGCUGCCAUCAAGCCCUGCUCAGUUGAGCUGCAGAAGUCUUUCUAAGAAGGAGAGAACAAGCAUAUUUGAAAUGUCUGAUUUUUCCUGCGUUGGCAAAAAAACCAGAACAGUUGACAUUACCAAUUUCACAGCAAAAACCAUCUCCAGUCCUCGGAAAACUGGAAAUGGUGAAGGCCGUGCAACUUCGAGUUGCGUGACUUCUGCCCCUGAAGAAGCCCUAAGGUGUUGUAGACAGGCUGGGAAAGAAGACGCAUGCCCAGAGGGAAAUGGCUUUUCUUACACCAUUGAGGACCCUGCUCUUCCAAAAGGACAUGAUGAUGAUUUAACUCCUUUGGAAGGAAGCCUUGAAGAAAUGAAAGAAGCGGUUGGUCUGAAAAGCACACAGAACAAAGGUACCACUUCCAAAAUAUCAAACUCCUCUGAAGGCGAAGCCCAGAGUGAACAUGAGCCAUGUUUUAUAGUUGACUGUAACAUGGAGACGUCUACAGAAGAGAAGGAAAACUUACCCGGAGGAUACAGUGGAAGUAUGUGAAUCUCCUUUUCCAAGUCACCUUCGCUAAAUAAACAUGUAACAGUGCAUCCAUAUUUUAAAUUUAUCACAACUUUUUCAUAACUUAUUUCCCCAUUUACUCCUCUUUUUACUUAAAGAAUGUGCAUUUGAUCAUUCCAAUGAUAAACUCUUUAGGAAUAGAUGACUUGCUGUCUUGUGGAACUUCUAGACUUAUUGGUUAAGUCUGUUAGGAAUCUAUUUCUCCAAGACUUUUCCUUCUUAUAGGUCAAAAGGAUAAGUAGUCCAUAGUAUGAAUAACUGAGGGGAGUGAAGUCUUUUUCCUUAUUCCAUUGGAGUCUUGGCGCUGCAGCGUGUGUAAAGAUGUAUACGAUAGAGAGUUUUUUAAAACCUAGGUUCUUAAUAGUGAGGCUAUUUAAAGAAAGAAAUUAAGGUAGAUUAAGCCAUCGAUUGUAUCAUAGAGAAAGUGUGAAAAACUACUUUUAGAAAUCUGUUGUCAAUAUUGAUUUUUGAAGAAACUUUGGUCAGUGUUAACUAUGAAGAAACAUUUAAACAUUUUUGAUCAUUUGUAACAAGCCUUGUUUAACUUGUACUUAUUUUGCUUGAAGCAUCACUUGAAAAGGUUUACUCCUAUUCAUAAUUUAAUUGUAAUUAUAAUAAACCAUAUCAUUUUAUUAAAAGUCAAAACAAUAAAAAAUUUUGCACUUCACAGUUAUAAGCACAAAUAGGUUCCAGCAACCAAAAUUGAAGAAAUCUUGAACUUUGACCGUCUUUACCUAAAGAUUAGGUUAAAAUUUGAGUGAGAACGCAUUCUCUCUGCAUGAUUUCUCUGCUCUACAAAUGUUUUAACUGCCUCUUUGAAGGUGGAGAAGUCAUGGUAGCGUUUGAAAUCAUCACAGACAUGUUACAUACCUUUUCCUUGAGUAUACGCUCCCCAAAAUUGUUUCACAAAAAGAAUGAAAAUAAUUUUAUGUUUUUGGCCUGCUAUUUAUAUCUUGGCUUUCUGAACAUAUAUUAAAUUUGACAAGAAACUGUAUUUUAUGUUCCAUUAGCCUUAGUAUGUGUUUUCAAAAUAUUUAUUUUAAAAUGUUGACUCAAAAGUUAAUAUAAAACAAUAGAUGUGUAAAAUUCUUUGGUAGUUAAGAAUAUCCUGUUCUGAGGUUUACAUUCUCCAUCUUUCCAGUUUUCACCUUGUGUAUUUUUUAAGCUUUUGAAUAAUAAUGACAUGGAAAUGUAAAUUAAGUAGGAAAAAGCUGGUAGCAAACAGUGUGGCAUGGCCUAAAAUCCCCGUGUUGCUGGGAGUGUGCUAGUCCUCGGAAGCAGGUGUGUUAUGUUCUAGAACACUGCCCCCCUGCGUCGACAGCCUCCGGGGUUGGGGGUAAGUAGAAGGGGGUGAGGGGCCAGCACUAGUUGACUCAAGGCACCCUGGUGGGGACGGAGAGGUUUUUUCGCUCAGUGGUGCAGGCCAUCAGGCAGGGGUGUCCAGGCAGGGCCCGGGUGCAAGAAAACAUUCUGUGUGCGCUAGUGCGAGAGGAUCUUCUACAGUCACCUGCCUUCAUGCCAUUACAGACAGACGGGAAGUCACUGGGUUCUAGGACAUAAAAAGACCUACAUGUUGGCUAGCCUAAAUCGAACCCUUUUAUAGUAAUAAAGAUUCAUCAAUGUUUUAAACUGUCCACUGUCAGCCCCCUGGGACUCAGGUGAACCAACUCUCUUUGGGAAUCUAUCUUAGAAGAUGAAACCAUAAAGCCUUCAGUUUCAAUGUCAGGGAUGCACACUCUAUAUCUGGUGAAAUUAUGGAGGGGUGAAAACUUCUGUACAGCAAACUGUACCUCCAAAUCUUUAAUGUCGAAAUAAAGGGCUUUUUGCCA